AGUGGCUGUGGUGGUGGUGGUGGCGGCGGCAGCCUCAGCUCCUGCUCCCCGUGCCGCCGGCCCCAGCGCUGUCUCCCGGGCCCCCUAGGGCCCCCGGGCCCUCAAGCCCGGUGCGCGCCCUCGCGUCCCGCCGGCCCCCUCCCCCGGCUGGGCCCGGGGGAGGGUGGCGCCGUGAGAGAGCGGGGACAGGGCUCUCCUGCCCGUUCCCCUGCCCCUGGGCCGCCAGGAUGGAGGCGGGGUCGGGGCCCCCGGGCGGCCCGGGAUCCGAGAGCCCAAAUCGGGCCGUGGAGUACCUGCUGGAGCUGAACAACAUCAUCGAGAGCCAGCAGCAGCUGCUGGAAACCCAGCGGCGGCGCAUCGAGGAGCUGGAGGGCCAGCUGGACCAGCUCACCCAGGAGAACCGCGACCUGCGAGAGGAGAGCCAGCUGCACCGCGGGGAGCUGCACCGGGACCCCCACGGCGCGCGGGAUAGCCCGGGCCGCGAGAGCCAGUACCAGAACCUGCGCGAGACCCAGUUCCACCACCGCGAGCUGCGGGAGAGCCAGUUCCACCAGGCGGCCCGGGACGUGGGCUACCCGAACCGGGAAGGCGCCUACCAGAAUCGGGAGGCUGUGUAUCGGGACAAGGAGCGGGACGCCUCCUACCCGCUCCAGGACACUACCGGUUACACAGCCCGCGAGCGUGACGUGGCCCAGUGCCACCUGCACCACGAGAACCCAGCCCUGGGUCGCGAGCGUGGCGGGCGGGAGGCCGGGCCGGCGCACCCGGGCCGCGAGAAGGAAGCGGGCUAUUCGGCGGCGGUGGGCGUGGGGCCGCGGCCACCGCGGGAGCGGGGCCAGCUGAGCCGUGGCGCAUCCAGGAGCUCCAGUCCCGGCGCCGGCGGAGGCCACAGCACCAGUACCAGCACCAGCCCGGCCACGACCCUCCAGAGAAAAUCUGAUGGUGAGAAUUCCAGAACAGUCAGGUCCACAGCGUCUCAUACUCUACACCAGUAUUGCUGUCCUACUCAGGUCCUUGACUCCAUGAAGCUUACCCCCUCAGGCAGGCUGGCAGAGAGCAGUGUGGAGGGUGAUGCCCCAGGCAGUGACCUGAGCACAGCGGUUGAUAGUCCUGGGAGCCAACCCCCCUACCGGCUGAGCCAGCUGCCCCCCUCCAGCAGCCACAUGGGGGGCCCCCCUGCUGGAGUGGGCCUUCCCUGGGCUCAGCGGGCACGCCUCCAGCCAGCCAGUGUCGCCCUGAGGAAGCAGGAGGAGGAGGAGAUAAAGCGCUCCAAGGCCCUAUCGGACAGCUAUGAACUCUCCACAGACCUGCAGGACAAGAAGGUGGAAAUGCUGGAGAGGAAGUAUGGGGGCUCCUUCCUGAGCCGCAGGGCUGCCAGGACCAUCCAGACAGCCUUCCGCCAGUACCGCAUGAACAAGAACUUUGAGCGGCUACGCAGCUCAGCCUCAGAGAGCCGCAUGUCCCGCCGCAUCAUCCUUUCCAACAUGCGGAUGCAGUUCUCCUUUGAGGAGUAUGAGAAGGCACAGAACCCCGCGUACUUCGAGGGCAAGCCUGCCUCGCUGGACGAGGGUGCCAUGGCUGGUGCCCGGAGCCACCGGCUUGAACGGGGGCUCCCAUAUGGAGGCUCCUGUGGUGGGGGCAUCGAUGGUGGUGGAAGCUCCGUCACCACAUCUGGAGAGUUUUCUAAUGACAUCACAGAACUUGAGGACUCCUUCUCCAAACAGGUAAAGUCUCUGGCUGAAUCCAUCGACGAAGCCCUGAACUGCCACCCGUCAGGGCCCAUGUCUGAGGAGCCAGGGUCAGCCCAGCUGGAGAAGCGGGAGUCAAAGGAACAGCAAGAGGACAGCUCAGCCACAUCCUUCAGUGAUCUUCCCCUCUACCUGGAUGACACAGUUCCCCAACAAUCCCCUGAGCGACUGCCCAGCACAGAACCCCCACCCCAGGGCCGGCCCGAGUUCUGGGCGCCAGCCCCUCUCCCGCCAGUUCCUCCACCAGUGCCAUCAGGAACCCGGGAAGACGGUAGCCGUGAGGAAGGCACUCGCAGGGGUCCCGGGUGCUUGGAGUGCCGGGAUUUCCGGCUGCGGGCUGCCCACCUUCCCCUGCUUACCAUUGAGCCUCCUAGUGACAGCUCCGUGGACCUGAGUGACCGCUCAGAUCGCGGCUCUGUCCACCGCCAGCUGGUGUAUGAGGCUGAUGGCUGCAGCCCCCAUGGGACCCUGAAGCACAAGGGGCCACCAGGCAGGGCCCCGAUCCCACACCGCCACUACCCAGCCCCUGAAGGCCCAGCCCCAGCCCCACCAGGGCCCCUGCCACCAGCCCCCAACAGUGGCACUGGGCCCAGUGGUGUGGCUGGGGGUCGGAGGUUGGGGAAGUGCGAGGCAGCAGGCGAGAACUCUGAUGGUGGAGAUAACGAGAGCCUUGAGAGCUCCAGCAAUUCCAAUGAGACCAUCAACUGCAGCUCCGGCUCCUCUUCUCGGGACAGUCUAAGGGAGCCUCCGGCUACCGGCCUGUGCAAGCAGACUUACCAGCGGGAGACAAGGCAUAGCUGGGACUCGCCAGCUUUCAACAAUGAUGUGGUCCAGAGGCGGCACUACCGAAUCGGCCUCAACCUCUUCAACAAGAAGCCAGAGAAGGGUAUCCAGUAUCUGAUCGAGCGGGGCUUCCUGUCAGACACACCGGUGGGAGUGGCUCACUUCAUCCUGGAGCGGAAAGGCCUCAGCCGGCAGAUGAUAGGGGAAUUCCUAGGGAACCGGCAGAAGCAGUUCAACAGAGACGUGUUGGACUGUGUGGUGGAUGAGAUGGACUUCUCCUCCAUGGAUCUGGAUGAUGCGCUCCGGAAGUUCCAGUCCCAUAUCCGGGUUCAGGGUGAGGCCCAGAAAGUGGAGCGACUCAUCGAAGCCUUCAGCCAGCGGUACUGUGUCUGUAACCCAGCCCUCGUGCGCCAGUUCCGGAACCCAGACACCAUCUUCAUCCUUGCUUUUGCCAUCAUCCUCCUCAAUACCGACAUGUACAGUCCCAGCGUCAAAGCUGAACGAAAGAUGAAACUAGAUGACUUCAUCAAGAACCUGAGAGGGGUUGACAAUGGUGAAGACAUCCCCCGAGACCUCCUGGUGGGCAUCUACCAGCGCAUCCAGGGGCGUGAACUGCGGACCAACGAUGACCAUGUGUCCCAGGUGCAGGCUGUGGAGCGCAUGAUUGUUGGAAAGAAACCAGUCCUGUCUCUCCCUCACCGUCGACUGGUUUGCUGCUGCCAGCUCUACGAGGUGCCAGAUCCAAACCGCCCCCAGAGGCUAGGGUUGCAUCAGCGGGAGGUCUUCCUCUUCAAUGAUCUCCUUGUGGUCACCAAAAUUUUCCAGAAGAAGAAGAUCUUGGUGACGUACAGUUUCCGUCAGUCUUUCCCCCUCGUGGAAAUGCACAUGCAGCUCUUCCAGAAUUCAUAUUACCAGUUUGGGAUCAAGUUGCUGUCUGCAGUACCUGGUGGGGAGCGAAAAGUCCUCAUCAUCUUCAAUGCCCCCAGCCUCCAGGACCGGCUGCGCUUUACAUCCGACCUGCGCGAGUCCAUUGCGGAGGUGCAGGAGAUGGAGAAAUACCGUGUGGAGUCGGAGCUGGAGAAGCAGAAAGGUAUGAUGCGGCCUAACGCCUCACAGCCUGGAGGGGCCAAGGACUCAGUGAAUGGGACGAUGGCCCGCAGUAGCCUGGAGGACACUUACGGGGCAGGCGAUGGGCUCAAACGGGGCGCACUCAGCAGUUCCCUGCGAGACCUCUCUGAUGCAGGGAAGCGGGGGCGGCGUAACAGCGUGGGAUCGCUGGACAGCACCAUCGAAGUGUCCCAGGGAAGACAACUAGCAAAAGCAGCAGCUGGGGCCACCUACGCAUUUGAUGCCGCCUCAUGGACCAGACUUGAGGGUUUGAAGAGCUUAGACCCACAGGGUCCUGAAUCAAGUCCAAUCAACAUUUUUUAGUUUUCUUCCCUGCUGGACCAAGCUGCACGAUCAUUUCCCCACCUUCAACUUGAUUCUGGUUGCAUUUUUCCAAAGCUCAGCUUUUAGCGCUCAAAUCCUGGCUCGGUGACUUGCCUGUGCUGCAUUUGGCAAGUCACCUAGCCCUUCAGAGCCUGGCCUUCCACCUGUAAGAUGGGGAUAACAACCUUGCAGGACAGUUAACAGAUGCAUGUGAAGUGCCUACCUCAUGCCAGACACACAGUAAGCCACCUACAGAAACCCCUUAUCUUGACAUGGGAGGUGUUCCACAAGGUGGCCCAGCCAAUCUCUGUGGUCCUAACUCUCAUUCCUCACCCACACAUUGGCCAUCCACUUACUAUUCCCCAAAAAUGCCUCUGUGUACUUUCCAAACUCAGCAUUUUACUUGUGGCUUUCCCCCCUGCCACAAUACUCCCCCCAACAUCCCUGAUGAAGGUUUUCCCAACCCUUGCAAGAUGGGCUUGAAGAACCCAUCCUUCACAAAAUGUGCCCUUCAUCACAUACUCUGAGAUCCUUCCCCACCAGGCCUUAAGUGGCUUGGGAGUGACACUGGUCUGAAUCAUCUCCAUCCAGAACAUUGCCCCAUAUAGUGCCUGGCACAGCACAGAUGGCACUAAAAUUUUGUUGAUCAAAUGAAUGAAUGAAUGAAUGGUUCUAAGUCUCAGAGUUAGAUAUCUUUGCAUUGGUUGAUUUAUUGAUUGAUGCAACCUGUGUACCAAGUUUCCGGGCCCCUCUGGGAGCUCCUCAUGCUUCCUUCAACUGUUUCCUACGUUCUUCUCCUCCAGUCCUCAUUGCAGUCCCAGCGCUGGGCUGUCCAUGCUCCUCACUCCCUCCACCCCUCCAGAAAUGCACUGUCCAGACUGUGGAGGGGGUAGUUCAUCUCCUCACCUCCCCAUUUCUCUGAGGACCCAAAGACAGCAAGCCCACUGACUAUUCUUACAUCAAAGGUGCUGCUGCCAAUCCCUCUGGGGAUGCAGAUGGGGACAGACAACACAUAACAAAGAACAGAACUGCUUGAACCCGAGAGGCGGAGGUUGCAGUGAGCUGAGCGAGCUCGCGCCACUGCACUCCAGCCUGGGUGACAGAGCAAGACUCUGUCUCAAAAACAAACAAACAAACAAAAACAAAGGACAAAGGUCCUAGCAUCUCAGAGUUCUUAUGUUUGUUCUCUAGUGCUGUCCAAUAGGUCUGUCUGUGAUAAGCAAAAUGUCCCAUACCUGUGCUGUUCAGUACGGUAACCACUAGCCACAUGUGGCUACUGAGCACUCGAAACAUGGCUAGUGCAACUAAGGAACUGCACUUUUCAUUUUAUUCAAUGUAAAUGUAAAUAAAUAAGCACAUGUGGGUAAGUAGCUGCCACGUCAGACAGUGUAGGAUAAGAGUUUCAGGAGUGGACAGAGCCUGGUGGGGAUAAUGUGAAGAUGAUAAAAUAAGUGCAGGCCCAGAAGGAAGCCCUGGGUAUGUGGGAACACAGAGGAGGGGAAAACCCAACUUGGGGUGUGUGGGUGGGGUCAGGCACCAUUUUCUGGAGCCGCUCCUUUUAGUGGAGUAGUCUUGAAGGGCGAGUAGGACUUAGCCUGAUAGAGAAGGGAGGGAGGGAGCAGCGCAUGAAAAGGCCUGGAGAUGCGAGAGAAUGCAAUGUGUUAGUGGCACCGUAAGAAAGGAAUGGGAGCUGGAGCUCCAGCGGUGGGCACAGCACAUGGCACCGCGUGGAGACAGGCGGGUCUCCCCAGCCACUCCCUGUUACUCUGUUGCCAACAGAUUUGUCACGCUGGCCUCAGCAGCAGCUAAAGUAAGACCAGAUAACAAAUUGGGCUAUCUAGUACCUGCACUGUAAAGUUACCACUUUCCCCGUUGUAGUGGAUGAGUAUCUUGUGGAGACAUGAAUGGAAAUGUUGUUACUCCUUAAAUUUUACUCACUAGUUUUAGCGUUCGCUGGAACAAUUAUUAUGGCUGAGGCUGUCAAAUGGUGAUUUUCAAAUGCCGUCAUUCUUUCAAUAUGUCUUUUUUUUUUCUUUUUUGAGACAGGGUCUCAUCCAUUGCCCAGUGCAGUGGUGCGAUCAUAGCUCACUGCAGCUUCGAACUCCUGGAUUCAAGCGAUCCUCCCACCUCAGCCUUCCAUGUAGCUGGGACCACAGCCACACACCACCAUGCCCAGCUAAUUUAAAAAUUUUUUGUAGAGAUGGAGGUCUUGCUAGGUUACCCAGGCUGGUUUCAAACUCCUGGCCUCAAGCAGUCCUCCCACCUCAGCCUCCCAAAGUGUUGGGACUAUAGGCAUGAGCCACUGCCCCCAGCCUGGGCAUGUCUUAGUUGGCUUUCCACUAUAAGGGAGGGCUUUCCCUUCUACAUUUAUUUAUUUAUAUCCUUAUGGACUUAAUGAUUGUUUAUUUUACUCAAUGGGUUAUAUAUAACCCAUUAACAUCAUUCUUUAUUUUGAUGUUCACAGCCCCAGAUUUGGCCAGUAGGAAGCCCUCUAAGCCCCUGUGUCCUGUGGCACAUCUCCAUCUUUUUCUGAGCCCUUCCAAGGAGCCCCGGUUCUUUUUAGUAGAGAAUGACAUUUAGAAACCAAGAUUUGGGCACUAGGUGUUACAGCAAUAUUUUAAGAGCUUGCUCUUUUAUUUUGCAAAGGUUUGAGCAUCCAUUGAUGAUUUCUAGCUCCAUCAUUCCUUCUAUAUAAUUUAGAAUUCUACUUUCCCUUUUCUCUCACUUUAUUUACUUAUAUCAAUGUGGAGUCAUGGAUUUUUAUUUUAACCAGUGAGUUGUAAUCCACUACUAUCAUAAUUCAUUUUGAAUUAACAUUACUUUGGAUAAAUCAUUUUAUUGUUAUGUAUAUGUAUAAGCACAUACUAUACAUCUAUAUUUCUAUACUAGACAUCGAUAUUUCUCUGUCUCUGUCUAAUAAACCAUGAGUUCACACAGAUACCUUGAGGAGGCUCUUUUAAGAGUCCAGGCUAGAGACAGUAAAAGGCUCACAGGAGGAGUGGAAGAUGGCAAGGAGGAGGGGAUGGAUUCUAGAGCUAUUUAGGAAUCAGAACCAACAGCUUAAACCUACUUCAGAACUGGAAGAGAUCAUAUUUUACAAACCAAAAAAAGUGAGACACAAAGUCAGUGUCAGCCCAGUUGAUCCACAAAACAUGAAUGGGGUGCGUGUGGUUUUGAGCCCAGACGAGCCUUCCAGUCACUGCUCUGCACCAACUCCAUGUCAGACCCUGUCUCCCGGGUGGAUGGGUGAGGCCAAGCCAGCCCCCAGCCUGGAGUGAGUUUCCUGAUGCAUCCCAAUUCUUAAGUCCCCAGCGUCUAGACUCCGGUUGUCCCCCAGCAAGACCCAUGGCUUGGGGAACAAACCCAUUUCCUGAAUGCCUUACUACAUGGGGAGCACCAUCUGAGACUCUUACAGGCAGAAUUGUACGGCAGUCAGACAGACCUGGGUUUGAGUUCUGGUCCUGCCACUUACUAGCCAUGUGACUUGAGUAAGUUUACACUUCCCUGAGCUUCAGUUUCCUCAUCUGUAGGAUGGGGAUAACAAUACCUACUUCAUAGCACCUGGCCCUUGAUGAAUGGCAGUCAUCAUUAUCUCUAAUCCUCCUAACAACACUGUGAGGAAGGGAUUAUUUAGCUUCAUUAUACAAAGGAGAAAAUCAAGGCUCAGGAAGAUGAGGUACUUGGCAGAUCUCAGUGGGUGCAUGUCAGCUCCAGGAAAGUAGAGACUACAUCUGUCUUGGUCACCAUUAUAUUCCCAGUGCCCAGAAAAUUUGCUGGUGCAUAGUAGAAAUUUAAUAAAUAUUUGUAAACGAAUAAAUUCUAUCUCAUUGGCUUCAAA